AGAACCCCGCGGGGUCUGAGCAGCCCAGCGUGCCCAUUCCAGCGCCCGCGUCCCCGCAGCAUGCCGCGCCCCCGCCUGCUGGCCGCGCUGUGCGGCGCGCUGCUCUGCGCCCCCAGCCUCCUCGUCGCCCUGGAUAUCUGUUCCAAAAACCCCUGCCACAACGGUGGUUUAUGCGAGGAGAUUUCCCAAGAAGUGCGAGGAGAUGUCUUCCCCUCGUACACCUGCACGUGCCUUAAGGGCUACGCGGGCAACCACUGUGAGACGAAAUGUGUCGAGCCACUGGGCCUGGAGAAUGGGAACAUUGCCAACUCACAGAUCGCCGCCUCGUCUGUGCGUGUGACCUUCUUGGGUUUGCAGCAUUGGGUCCCGGAGCUGGCCCGCCUGAACCGCGCAGGCAUGGUCAAUGCCUGGACACCCAGCAGCAAUGACGAUAACCCCUGGAUCCAGGUGAACCUGCUGCGGAGGAUGUGGGUAACAGGUGUGGUGACGCAGGGUGCCAGCCGCUUGGCCAGUCAUGAGUACCUGAAGGCCUUCAAGGUGGCCUACAGCCUUAAUGGACACGAAUUCGAUUUCAUCCAUGAUGUUAAUAAAAAACACAAGGAGUUUGUGGGUAACUGGAACAAAAACGCGGUGCAUGUCAACCUGUUUGAGACCCCUGUGGAGGCUCAGUACGUGAGAUUGUACCCCACGAGCUGCCACACGGCCUGCACUCUGCGCUUUGAGCUACUGGGCUGUGAGCUGAACGCAAGGAAGGCAGACUUGAGGCGAGGAGCAGAUGACAGAGAGCAGUAACAGCUCUGAAGAAAAGCUAGAGGCUGAUGAGAUGACCAUGACUUGGGGUGAGGGGAGAGAGCAAGACAAGGACUGCUCUGUCGGGAAGGCCUUUGACUGGGGGCCUGAAUGAUGGAGAGCCAGCCACAUGAAAAACUUAAAAACAGCACUGCAAAAAGAGCACUGCAGGCAAGGAAUUGGUAAAUGCAAAGGCCCUGGGGCAUGUUGAAGGGUGGAAGGAAGGCCAGUGGAGCUGGAGCCAAGAGAUGGAGGGGCAGCUUGGUGGGUGAAGAGCCCCAGGGACCCGCAGUGUCAUCACCUAGGAGCUUCUUAGAAAUGCAGACUGAGGCCGGGUGCGGUGGCUCACGCCUGUAAUCCCAGCACUUUGGGAGGCCGAGGCGAGCGGAUCACCUGAGGUCAGGAGAUCAAGACCAGCUUGGCCAACAUGGCGAAGCCCCGUCUCUACUAAAAAAAUACAAAAAUUAGCCAGGCGUGGUGGCAGGUGCCUGUAAUCCCAGCUACUAGGGAGGCUGAGGCAGGAUAAUUGCCUGAACCCGGUCAGAAGGUGGAGGUUGCAGUGAGCCGAGAUCAUGCCACUGCACUCCAGCCUGGGUGACAGAGCGAGACUGUGUCUCAAACAAACAAACAAAAAAACAAAAAAAAAGAAAUACAGACUGAAAGCCCCAGCCUAGACUUGCUGAAACAUAAGCUUUUUUUUUUUAUAUCAAGAUCCCCAGGUGAUCUGUGAGAAUUACUCCCCUAGUAUCUCAUUUUAUAGAUGGGGAGACUGAGAGCCAGAGAGAGGAAGGGACUUCCUAGAGUGCUGGAGCUGACAGUCCUGUCCCUGCCCUGGUGCCCCUUCCAACUGCAUUUUACCAGAAAGGCUGUCUGACUUCCUGGGGAGGCUGAGAGUGAGGAGGGUAUGAACCACUAGAAGCAGAUGAUCUGUAGAGGGGUCUGCGUUGAGCACAUUGUGCAGAAUUGGUGUCCUCUGCAAAGCUGCCCAGGUUUUAGCCUGCCUCAGGCCUCUCCUCUUCUGGGGCCAAGGGACAACCAGCUCUCAGCCCGGGAGCCUCUCUUUGAGGGGGAAGGUGGUGGUUCCCUGGUGCAUCACCAUCAGGAGAUGAUGGUACCAUCAGCAGGCAUUGUCAACACACCCUGGAGGCAAAUGUCUUGAGUGGUGAGAGUACAGGUGGGCAGUGAUAUAACUUAGCUGGCUCCCAGUACUCUUGAGUGGUGAGAGUAUUGGAGGGCAGUGAUAUAACUUAGCUGGCUCCCAGAGGGCAGGGGGCUCUCCAGUCCCACCGUCCACUCCUGCCUCCCUCAAUUCCCCAGAGGGAUAGACACUUGUGGAGUGAGGAUUCUUCCAGGUGGGAGACACCCCCAUCAUUCUCUUGGGAGUUGUAUCUCUUGCCCAUCCCCAACUGUUCUAUCCAUAUGCAGGUGCAGAUACAAGUGCAAGGCAGCCCGGCACAUUCCUGAGUGUUUGGGGCAGGGCUGAGUGAAACAAAGGCCAGCUUCCCGGGCCAGCCCUCACAGGCCUGUGUGACAGCAUCCCCAGAACAUUUGAGUGUGCGAAGGCCCUCUGGGAGACACUAAGUCAGGGGGCUUCUGGGGAAUGGAAAUAGAGAUGUUCCUGUGCCCCAGGAGUUGUCUGAUUUCUCUAACUGCCAGCUGCUGGAGGGCAGGGAUGUUGUCCUGUUCAUCACUGGGUCGUCACUAGGCAGGCCUUCAUCAUCUAGCUGGGAUGUGUAGCUGGUAGAGGUGACGUCAUAGUGUGACAUUAGGAGUUUGUAUGUGACUUGAGCAUGAUGCUUAAUGUCUUUCAGUUUUCUCAUCUAUAGAAUGGGCUUACUAAUUUCUACUUCAUUUAGUGUUUUUUUUUCUUUUUUUUUUUGGUGGCAGGUUAAAUGACUGAAGUAAGCACUGAAUAAACAAUGUGGUUGUUAUUAAA